UGUUUGGUGAUAAUCCCCUUCCGUGCCCAGGGUGUGGAGAACAAGGUUAGGGCCCCAUGUGGGAAAGGCAAUGGCUCUGAUCCCUGCAGGCCUGGGCCUCGGUCUCUCACUUCUGAUCCCCCGCCAGACACCCCUAGCCUGUCCCCUUCCCUCCCCUCCCCAGGGCCUGCCAGGCUGGGUGUCUCUGAGCCCACCUGCCCACCUAUCCCAGCCCCCAGGCAGUCCGAGCCUCAGUCUCCCAGCUCCCUGUGGCCUCUGGGUGCCUGGCCUCUGUCUCAGCCUCUCAGCCUCCUGUCUGUUCCUCUGUCUUUGCAGCAACUUCUCUGUGCCGAGCGCCUCCCCUAGGCUGACUGUCCUCUCUCUGCCUCUGUCCUGUCCUCUAUUUCUUUGUGACUGAGUCUUCAUCUGUCCCUAAGCCCCCUCUCCUGCCCAGCCCUGCUUGUCUCUGUGUCCCUCUCUAGGUUUCCACGUCUGCUGGCCUUGGCCAGCCCCUCUGCUCCAGCCGCUCACCGCUCCCCAGGGCCCCCUGCCCCUCGACACUGACGGAUAACUCUGGGGUGUUAAGCUACGGAUUAGUUCAGGCAAAAUUCUCGAUUUUGUCUGCGUUCUUUCCCCUUUGGGUUAUGUAAACAGUAAUUCUCCCCAGAUGGAACUAUUUUCCUCGCUUCCAUGCAGCCGGGGAGGGGGCCUGGACGGGUUGGGGGUGGAAUGCCCCAGUUCCACAGGACACCUCCAGGAGGGGUAGAGGCUGCGGCUGAGAUCCCCAGCCCAGCCACCUCUCUUCCCUCCAGGUGCUGGCUCUGCUGUGACCAUGCCCGUGACCUUUGCCCUCCUGCUCCUCCUGGGCCAGGCCACUGCGGACCCAUGCUACGAUCCACAGGGCCGCCCCCAAUUCUGCCUCCCGCCAGUGACACAGCUGGCUGCCGUGGCGGCCUCCUGCCCUCAGGCCUGUGCCCUGUCCCCAGGAAACCACCUUGGCGCCAGGGAAACCUGCAAUGGCAGCCUGACUUUGGCCCUGGGUGGCCCCUUCCUCCUGACAUCUGUCAGCUUGCGCUUCUGUACCCCAGGACCCCCAGCCCUCAUCCUGUCUGCUGCCUGGGCCUCAGGGGGUCCCUGGAGGCUGCUGUGGCACAGGCCCGCCUGGCCUGGGGCCUUAGGGGGCCCUGAAAGGGUGACCUUCCACUCCACACCAGGUCCUAAGGCCACUGUGGCGGCCAGCCACCUCCGUGUGGAGUUUGGGGGCCAGGCCGGGCUAGCGGCAGCUGGGCUGAGAGGCCGCUGCCAGUGUCAUGGCCACGCUGCCCGCUGUGCCGCCCGUGCCCGGCCCCCCCGCUGCCACUGCCGCCACCAUACCACUGGCCCGGGGUGCGAGAGCUGCCGCCCGUCCCAUCGAGACUGGCCCUGGCGGCCUGCCACGCCCCGGCACCCCCACCCUUGCCUACCCUGCUCCUGCAACCAGCACGCCCGACGCUGCCGGUUCAACUCUGAGCUGUUCAGACUGUCGGGCGGCCGGAGUGGGGGUGUUUGUGAGCGGUGCCGCCACCACACAGCUGGGCGGCACUGCCACUACUGCCAACCUGGGUUCUGGAGGGACCCUAGCCAGCCUAUCUUCAGCCGCAGGGCCUGCAGAGCCUGCCAGUGCCACCCUAUUGGGGCAACAGGAGGAACCUGCAACCAGACCAGUGGGCAGUGCACCUGCAAGUUAGGGGUCACAGGCCUGACCUGCAACCGCUGUGGCCCUGGCUACCAGCAGAGCCGCUCCCCCAGGAUGCCCUGCCAGCGAAUUCCAGAGGCAACAACCACCCUUGCCACUACUCCUGGUGCUUAUAGCUCUGACCCUCAGUGUCAAAACUACUGCAAUAUGUCGGACACCAGGGUACACAUGAGCCUUCGGAGGUACUGCCAGCAGGACCAUGAGUUUCAUCAUCUCCUUCAGCCUGACAUCUCUGAGGGAUGGAAGAGAUAGGGGAACUGGUUGAGUGGAAUGAACUCUUGCCCUGUCCUCCCUAUCUCAGAGACCCUUUCUGCUUCCCUUCAUGGUCCCAGAUAUUUGAGCCUUAGCCCCACUUCCCAUAAAGACUUGUCCCACGGUUCCCUAAUCCCCAGUCCACACCUGCUCCAUGACCUUGGGGUCUAUGACCUCAGGCUAUUCAGCUCUCUUAAGACACUCAGGAGUUCGGCCCAGCCAACAAAUCUAGACCAACGCCAGCUAUUUCUCUCAAUGUAUAGGACCGCAGACUUCUCCCUCAGGAACCUCAUCUGGUCACUAGUGUUCUAGGCCUUCACAGGUGGAAAGAUUUUCCCCACCUUCCACAGGGAUCUCCUGCCCCGCAGACCCAGCUGGCUAGUCAGAGUCCCACCCAGCCUCUCAGAAAGUGCAUUUUUCUGGCCGGGCGCGGUGGCUCAUGCUAAUAAUCCCAGCACUUUGUGGGGGCCGAGGUGGGCGGAUCACUUGAGGUCAGGAGUUCGAGACCAGCCUGGCCAACAUGGUGAAACUCCAUCUCUACUAAAAAUACAAAAAUUAGCCAGGCGUGGUGGCAGGAUCCUGUAAACCCAGCUGAGGCACAAGAAUCACUUCAACCUGGGAGGCAGAGGCUGCAGUGAGUUGAGAUCACACCACUGCACUCCAGACUGGGCAAUAGAGUAAGAUUCCGUCUCAAAAAAAAAAUUUAUGUUUUUCUGAAUCACUAUCAGUAUGACCUCAGCCCUCACAUUCCAGGGACCAGUCUCUUCCUUCUUCUGGUCCUCGAAAUUUAUCCCAGAGCCCCUCCCCCGGCAAUGUGACCCCUCCUUCCCAAGAAUUCCACCAUUGAUACCUUCUGACUCCACUGCAUUAGAGACCCUGGACCUGCCUCUUCUGCCCUGUCCCCAGCCCCACCUACUAUAGUUUAACUCCUUAUCUCAAAGAUGUUUCCUCCAGCAGGCUCUACCCCUCACGAUUUAGGGUCAAACUCUCCAAGGUUCAAGGUUUCUCUCCCCACUGCGAUACCAGAAGCCCACCCACCGGUCUCGGGCUCCUGCCCACUGUGACUGACCCCACGGGACCCAGAGGUACCCUGGAAGCUCCCCACGACCUGGGCUGACAUCUCCCCUCCCCACAGUUCUCCGCGCGCAGGUGCUAGCGUCCGAGGCGGCGGGCCCGGCAUGGCAGCGGCUGGC